UUCCAGGCUUUCAGUACGUCAAGAUGAAGAAAGAAGUAGGGUAAAAUCAUAUGUCUCUCUUUGAGUCAUUCCAUUAUCCAGAUACAAGCAAAACAAGGCUUCCAAAAUAGGACCAUAGUUCCCCAUACUAAGUAUAGCAUAAAUCUCCGAACACCCAGGACACCACAAAUUACAGGUUCCAGGCAGUUGACACAGGUCUCUCUGUUACAGCUACUAAUAUGGCUAGAAGGUAUGGUCACCUCUAAACAUGAUAAAUUUAUCCUAUCCUAAAUUAACAUUUGUCUUCUUAAAGUUCUUGAAAUAAUAAACCUCUUUACAUUAAUGUUUACUGGUUUAACAAUUAUUAAAAUAUAGCAUAUACUAAAAGGUAAGUUAACAAUUUUCCCUAUUGAAAUUUGAUCUGAUUUUCUCUGAGGAAGAAUUAAUAAAUAUGAUUACAAAGUUUUUGGUUUUUUUUUUUUUUUUUUUUUUUAACAUUUUUGGAAAAAACAUUCCAGAUCUAAAAGGAACUUGCAAGAGCCCUUGAUUGUCUUACAGAUGUGAAAACUGAGGGCCCAUAAGUUAGAUGAUCUCUCCAGGACGGUUAAAAAAAAAAAAAAUUCCCUCAUAAAGUUGAGCUUUGCCAAACAACUUUUAAUAAUUCUUACAUGGUUUGAGUACACUAUCUUUGGACUAAAUAACAACUCUCUCCUACACAGACUUAACUACAUGAAUUGUUAAGUGCCUCAAGUAAAAAAACCUGGAGAAUUAGGUUUCUGUUCUGCCUUUGCCACUAAUUAUGUGACCUUGGAUAAGUCACUUAAUUGAUUAUUGAAAUAUCCCUAACAUAGGAGGUUAGUUUACAUGAAAUCCAAAGUGCUCUGUGUCUUUAAAGUUCUGUAAGUCUAAGCAUUUGAAAACUACAGUAACAGAAAAAAAAAAAAACAACUACAGUGACAGAAAAUGUACAAUACUUCCAUUUUAUACCCACUGCUCCAGUUCUAACCACUUUGGAACAAUAUUUUAUAGUAACAUUAGGCUGCCAGAAGGCAAAUUGUCUAACCAUAACAAAUUGUGUGUGCAAGAGAGAUACAAGAAUAACAGGUGGUAUAAUAAUUCAGGAUAAAUAUGCACAACUCUCUCUCAAAAAAAGUCAAGUUCUUUCUUGAAUCUCUAAAUGCUUCAGGAUCCCUUACUUCCAGAAUUAUAGUCACCUUCUCCUUUGUAAUUCACCGCAAUAUUUUAUACACAUAUACAUGCACACACAAUUCAUGGUCAUAUUAAGGCUAGUUUCUAUAAUUGUCAGGGAGGACUGUUCUGUCUUUUCUAUUUAUAUGAAGCUAUUAUAGAUAAAAUCAGAGAGAAGAUUACAAUAAAAUGUAGACCACAUACGAAACCUAAAACUUGAAAAGUAAUUUACUCAGUGAGGGUUUUAAGUCCAUCACAUUUCUAUUCUAAAACAAAAGCUUGCAGAGAAUUAAAACACACACACACACACACACACACACCCGUUAUCAGUUUCUGCAGUGAACUUCUAUAUGAAGACAUAAAUAGAUGGCAAAUCAAUGGAAACUCAAGAGAAUCAUUUUCUUUCUUUGCUGUCCCUCAAAACACAAUUAAAAAGAUACAUAAAUAAUACAGGGGCCGGGCGCCAUGGCUCACACCUAUAAUCCCAGCACUUUGGGAGGCCGAGGCGGGCAGAUCACGAGGUGAGGAGAUCGAGACUAUCCUGGCUAACAUGGUGAAACCCCGUAUCUACUAAAAAUACAAAAAAGUAGUUGGGCGUGGUGGCAGGCGCCUGCAGUCCCAGCUACUCAGGAGGCUGAGGCAGGAGGAUAGCUUGAACCCGGGAGGCAGAAGUUGCAGUGAGCUGAGAUUGUGCCACUGCACUCCAGCCUGGAGACAGAGCGAGAAUCCGUCUCGAAAACCAAACAAACAAGAAAAAAAGUCAGAACAUGUUCUCAUUAAUUUGCAGAAUACAAAAAAAAGAUCAAAUCAAGGCCCGCAUGCCUACAGUCCCAGCUACUUGGGAUAUGGAGGCGGGAGGAUUGCUUGAGGCUAGGAGUUCUAGGCCGCAGUGCACUAUGAUAGCGCCUGUGAAUAGCUACUGCCCUCCAGCCUGGGCAACAUAGUGAGACCCUGUCUCUUUAAAAAAAAAAAAUCAAAAGAUGCCUUUCUUUGUACUUUAUUUUAUGAUGAAGUCAUGAGAAAGCAUUUGUUUCUGCAUUUGUUCACUUAUUUAUCUAUUGGAACUUUGCAGUCUAGGACAUUCUGCACUUCAAUAACUAAAGCCAAAGGGAAUUUAUUUUUUAAAAAAUCAAUGUUUACGUACUGAUAUCUGCAACUUACUUUGAAAUGUAUAUUUUUUUUUAAUGGAGAGAGGGAUGGAUGGAUGAUUAGAUGCAUGAUAAAAUAUAGUGAAAUGUUAGUUAUAGAAUCUAGUUGGUGGUUAUAUGGGUAUUCACUACAAAGUUCUUUCAACUUUUCCAGAUGUUGGAAAAUUUCAUAAUGAAAUGUUGAGCUAAAAUAAACGCUGGAAAUUUUGAUACAACUUUUAGAUAAAAAUUUCACCCUAUCUGGACAUUUCUACUGUCCAGGGAUCUGUUUGUAAAGGAGCAGGACCCAAAAACAUUACACAGAAAUCAUACCAAUGUCUUAACACUCUACAGAGCAGAAUGUACUGAGAUAAAUUGUUCUCCAGAGUACACAAAUCUGUGGGUAUCUGGAUCAUGUUAAGUCCCAAAUAAUUCAGAAAUAUGUGACACAACUCUAUGUAUACGUACACAUGUCAAAAUAGCAUGCAAAAGUUAUAUUUUAUAUAUAUCACGUAGGGCUUUACCAUCCCUCAGUUAUCAAUGAAUUAAAAAUACUAAGUUCCAAGAACCUUUUAACAAAGAAUAUUUUUAGAAAGAUUACCUUUAUCUGGUUUAUAUAAUACAAGACCUUAACUUUACUAUUAAAAUAAAAAUAUGCUCUAAAAUGCAUUAUUAAUUCCAGGGUGUAAACGGGAACUGAGUUUCAAAAUCACUAACCAAAUACAGAACCUCCUGGAGAAACUGAAAAUACAAGUUUCUGGAAAUUUUGUGUCCAACACAAAAAUUUUAGGAGGCAAACCUGUUUGAUGCAAUUUAUAUACCUGAGGCUGAGAAAAGCUGUUCAGUGGCCUAAAGUCCAAGCAUGAAUUCCCCCCAUUAUCCAAGUUCUUAUCUAAAGGGUUGUCAAUAGAACUUAUUAGGAUUGCCACCAAAUUACAUUCUGCCAUCUCUCAGGUACACUGGACGAUGUUUUAAAUCAAGUUAUCUAUUGACAAAAGAAUAAAAAAGAACAGAACAGAACAUCCUUCAAAAGACUAAAGGACAUAAGGUGCACUGAAAAAUAAAUUACUAGCUUUUUUGAAACCAAAGAAUGUCUACUACUUCAUGAAUAUCCACAAAUCACAGCGAUAAAGGAAGAUUGAGUGAUGUCAGCAGUUCUGAUUUCCUCCAUCCUCAACCACAUUAACCUUUCUCAUCCUUGUAACAGAUGAGUAUACAAAGAUAACGCAUGGGAAGGCAAGUAACUGGUCUCGGAGGCUAACCCAUCCCUCUUACUCCACCUCCUGUGAGACAUCUGACUACGACAUGCCACAUACACAUUUUUCUUCACCUGGACAAUAAGUUCCUUGAAGGCAAACCCUGUGUUCUCUGGAACCUGCUCACAUUUUCCCAGUGGUCUACACAGUGUAUGUACCCCGAGUCACACUAACAAAUGGACACAAGUGAGUUCUGCGGAAGUAGUGGAAGGUUUCAGAGACACUUGGGUCCUAUACAUUAGUGUUAGAAGUUACUCCUUUCCGCUCUGUGUCUCCAUUUCCCCCUUCUGAACAAAAAGAAAAAUUUCUGGACACCAGUGGAUUUGCAUUUCGAGUUAUCAACGGCCUAGCAAACACCGGGGGUGGGAGACAAGCUCUGAUUAACAGAAGGACCAGAACCUCCGGAGACAGGCCCAGCCUGCUGAGCCUAAGCGCCAGGGAACCGGCGGGACAGCAUCAGUUCCGAGGUCCGCAGCCUGGGACCCGCACCACCACCACGAAGUUCUCGCAGAGCAAAAACGCCGGGCCGUCUCAGGGGCAGGUCCCAGCAAACGAGGGAGUCCAGCUGGUUGGGGGGUGGUGCGGAAGCGGGCACGACGACAGAUGGACUGGAGUCAGCUCCAUCGGAUCUCCAGGAGACCGGGCACAGGAGGCCACACUGCUCCCCGAGCCCGGAGCAAAAGCACUCUGCCCUAGACCCUCAGGGCGGGGCUCCUCCGGCCCCUGCCCCAGGCCCGCCGACAAGGAGAGACGACCAAGGUUGUUGAAAACCAGACAUAUGAUGAGCGUCUAGAGAUUAACGACUCCGAAGAGGUUGCAAGUAUUUAUACUCCAACCCCAAGACACCAAGGACUUCCUCGUUCUGCCCAUCUUCCUAACAAGGCUAUGGCUGAUAACAGCAGUGAUGAGUGUGAAGAGGAAAAUAACAAGGUCCUAAGGGAGGGCAUGCCACAGGCUCCAGGCCACAGAGGCAAAGACAUGGACCCUGUUCCACCUGCCCCUGCAAGUCUCAAGUGCCACCAGACCCCUUCUCAUGUACUUGAGAGGGUGGGAUGGUACAGAGAGAGCCAGAAGCACAGAAAGGAGAAGAAGAAGACCUCACAGUUGACACCUCAACGGGGCUUUAGUGAAAAUGAGGAUGACGAUGAUGAUGAUGAUGAUUCAUCUGAAACUGAUUCUGAUUCUGAUGAUGAUGAUGAAGAGCAUGGAGCCCCUCUGGAAGGGGCCUAUGACCCUGCAGACUAUGAGCAUUUGCCAGUUUCUGCUGAAAUUAAGGAACUCUUCCAGUACAUCAGUAGGUACACACCUCAGUUGAUUGACCUGGACCACAAACUGAAGCCUUUCAUUCCUGAUUUUAUCCCAGCUGUCGGGGAUAUUGAUGCAUUCUUAAAGGUCCCACGUCCUGAUGGAAAGCCUGACAACCUUGGCCUAUUGGUAUUGGAUGAACCUUCUACAAAGCAGUCAGACCCUACGGUGCUCUCACUCUGGUUAACAGAGAAUUCUAAGCAGCACAACAUCACACAACAUAUGAAAGUAAAAAGCCUAGAAGAUGCAGAAAAGAAUCCCAAAGCCAUUGACACGUGGAUUGAGAGCAUCUCUGAAUUACACCGUUCUAAGCCCCCUGCGACUGUGCACUACACCAGGCCCAUGCCCGACAUUGACACGCUGAUGCAGGAAUGGUCCCCGGAGUUUGAAGAGCUUUUGGGCAAGGUAAGCCUGCCCACGGCAGAGAUUGAUUGCAGCCUGGCAGAGUACAUUGACAUGAUCUGUGCCAUUCUAGACAUCCCUGUCUACAAGAGUCGGAUCCAGUCCCUCCAUCUGCUCUUUUCCCUCUACUCAGAAUUCAAGAACUCACAGCAUUUUAAAGCUCUCGCUGAAGGCAAGAAAGCAUUCACUCCUUCAUCCAAUUCCACCUCCCAAGCUGGAGACAUGGAGACAUUAACCUUCAGCUGAGACACUUCCCAAGCUGCUGUUUCAAGGCUGAGCUGGCCCCUCUGCCCCAGCUGAGAUGGACAGAUCGUUGUCAGCUACUUGAUGUCCUUGCCCAUGCCACAGCUUGGCUCAGGGGCAGUGCAUGUCCUGCUGCCCUCUCUGCCAGAGGGCACAGAACAUGUUUGUUUAAUGAACCUGCCUGCCUCAGAUUGCUGUCCCCGGGGAGUUAAUGCAUCUACACCACUGUGGGGAUUUGAGUUAUAAGAAUUGGAAUUUCUGAGAUCCCAUGGAGGUUAGAUUGGGAGGAAAGCUUAAAAGAUGUCCUUUUUGUGAGAGGGAUGGAAUUGUUUUCUUUCAUUCGUAAAGUUAGUGAGUAAAGAUUUUAUAAAUCAAA